GUAGGGAGAGGAAGGAGAACCCCGGCGUGUUGAAGGCUCCGCGAAACCGGAGCGGUGGGGGACUACGCGGAGGGUGGGAGGGAUUCCGAGAGGAGGGUCGCGGGAGCCGUGGGCGCUCUCAGCCCGGUGUCCGCGGUGUAGGGGUUGGGGCGCGCCGGGCGGCGCCGUGAGAAACGGCGGGUCUCCAGCCUCUUCCGCAGGGAUGGUGGCGCCGCGGCGGCCGCGGAGCCCGGGGACCCCGCCCAGAGAGCCCGCAAGCCCCGGGGUCGCCGGCGCCCAGACCUGCCCGCGCCAGAGCUGUGGACCGAGCUGACCGGCCUGGCCGCCAGCUCCGAGCCUGAGGAUGGGUCGGAAGGCGCAGCCGAGGGCCGCGCGGCCGCGGUGUCCCUGGAAGAGGCCCUACUGCGCCUCGCCGAGUUCCUCUCCGUCCAGCUGGGGGCGGAAGAGAGCUGCGGGGGCCCGGCGGACCUGGGCCAGUCUGGCGAGGUCCCCUCACUGUUGACAGUGACCAGUCAGCUCUUGGCCCUUCUGGCAUGGCUUCGAAGCCCCAGGGGGAGGCAGGCCCUGCUCCAGGGGACUCAGCCAGCCCCUCGGGUCCGGCCCCCCUCUCCAGAUGGAUCCACAUCCCAAGAAGAAAGCCCUUCCCACUUCACCGCAGUCCCAGGCGAGCCACUGGGGGAUGAGACCCAGGGACAGCAGCCCCUCCAGUUGGAGGAGGAUCAGAGGGCGUGGCAGCGGCUGGAGCAGCUCAUCCUGGGACAGCUGGAGGAGCUGAAGCAGCAGCUGGAACAGCAGGAGGAGGAGUUGGGUCGACUGCGCCUGGGCGUGGGGGCGACGGACUCAGAGAAAAGGGUUCAGCAUCUGACUCUGGAGAACGAGGCCCUGAAGCAGAGCCUGAGUCUCAUGCGGGACCUCCUGCUGCACUGGGGCCCCGGGCCCCCCAUCAGGGCUCCGCAGGAGGAGGCAGAGGCAUUGCUAGAGCUCCAGGGCCGGCUUCAGGAGGCCCAAGACACCACAGAAGCCCUCCGAGCCCAGCUGGGGGUGCAGGAGGUGCAGCUGCAGGGCCUUCAAGGGGCCCUCCAGCAGCUCCAGCAGGAGACGGAGCAGAACUGCAGGCGUGAGCUACAGCAGAUGCAUGGGCAGCUGGCAGGACUUCGGGCACGGAUGGCCAGCCUGCGUCAGGGCUGCGGGGACCUCCGAGGUUUGGUCAGCACCUUUACCCAGAGCUGUCAGGGUUCGCUGAGUGAGGCCCGGGGCCAGGUGUCCUGGGCCUUGGGGGCACUGUCAUCUGGAGGGCCUGGCACUCAGCUCCCUGAGGGGCAGCAAGGGCCCCCAGCCGGAUGCCCAGGGCGGCUGCCAGAACUCAAGGGAAAUAUCCGUGUGCUGUGUCGGCUGAGGCCAGGGACAUCUUCUAGCCUUGUGAGUGUGGAGCCUGGCCCAGGGGGCACCGUCACCACCUGCUACCGGGGGCGCCAUCGUCGAUUCCGCCUAGACUGGGUCUUCCCUCCAGACGCCAGCCAGGAGGAGGUCUUCAGAGAGCUGGAACCUGCGGUGCUGUCCUGCCUCCGAGGCUACAGCGUCUGCAUCUUCACCUAUGGCCAGACAGGCACCGGGAAGACCUACAGCAUGGAGGGCCCUCCUGAGGACCCCGGCAUAGUUCCUAGGGCGCUGCAGUCGCUGUUCCGGGAGAUGGGGGCCGGCCGGCAGCACCGGGUGACACUCAGCAUGGUGGAGAUCUACAAUGAGGCUGUCAGGGACCUCCUUGCUCCAGGGCCUCCCGAGCGCCUGGCCGUGAGGCAGGGCCCAGAAGGCCAGGGCGGGAUCCAGGUGGCUGGCCUCACCCACUGGGACGUGCCCAACCUGGAGACAUUGCACCAGAUGCUGAAACUGGGGAGGAGCAACCGGGCCACCGCCGCCACCGCCAUGAACCAGCGCAGCUCCCGCUCGCAUGCCCUGGUCACGCUGACGCUGCGCGCGGCGUCUCCACCGCGCGCUCCAGGCACCGCAGGCACGCUGCACCUGGUGGACCUGGCGGGAUCCGAACGCGCACGGAAGGCAGGGGCGGCCGGCCCGCCGCGGGGAGACCCAGACGGCGCCCGGCGCCUGCGGGAGGCCCAGACCAUAAACCGCUCGCUGCUGGCGCUAGGAGGCGUGAUGGCCGCACUGCGGGCCCACCGGCCGCACGUGCCCUUCCGCGACUCGCAGCUCACGCGACUGCUGCAGCCGGCGCUGGGCCCAGGCACCACCGCGGUGCUGCUGCUGCAGGUGGGCGCCGGGGCGGGGCAGGUGUGUGCGUGCCGGUCGCCGCCCACCCGGGCCCGCCCACCCGCGCCUCUUGCCCGCAGAUCUCCACGCGGCCGGAGGAUCUCGGGGAGACAGUCUGCUCCCUCAAGUUCGCCGACCGAGUGGGUCAAGUGGAGCUGGGGCCAGCCCGGCGCCGCAGGGUCCCGCGCUCCUCCGGGACGCCUUCUUCCCUCAGCACCGACACUCCGCUCACCGGGACCCCCUGCACCCCUACGCCGUCCCCUGGCAGUCCUCCAUGCCCCAGUCCCGACAACGGCUCGGGCUCGGCUCUCGCGCCCGCAGAGGGCCUGCCCCUCUAGUCCUGGGUCGCGGCCCUGCCCAUGGGGUCUCAGGCCAGGUCUCUGCUGGCAGAGGCGGUAGUAAAGUCCCUGUACCCCGUCUCCCAGGGCACAAGCUCCCUAGCCUCUUUGGAUCCAUUGCCCCUGAGCUCCCAGAGUCACCCCUCCACCUCCGCAGCCAGUGAAGUGUGUUGUGCCUGCUGAAGUGAUCACCCCCCGCCCCCAGCCCUGCAUCAGGCCACAGGUCUUGGCUUUCUCCUUAUCACCAUUUGCUGUUAUCACGGCACACAGCAGGGAAUCCCAGGCCCCCCCGCCAAGUGGUUACCCAAGUCACCACUCCUGACCCAAAAAUCAGGCAUGGCAUUAAAACGUUGCAAAUUCCUUUACUGUUAUCCCCCCCACCACCAGGACCAUGUAGGGUGCAGUCUUUACUCCCUAACCCGUUUCCCGAAAAAGGUGCUACCUCCUUUCCAGACAGAUGAGAGAGGGCAGGACUUCAGGCUGGAUCCACCACUGGGCUCUCCCUCCCCCAGCCUGGAGCACGGGAGGGGAGGUGACGGCUGGUGACUGAUGGAUGGGUAGUGGGCUGAGAAGAGGGGACUAGGAAGGGCUAUUCCAGGCUCAGCCCUGCUCCUGCAGCUUUGCCGCUGAGUGUAGGAAAAACAGGCAUGACAGACCAGGGUGAGGGUUGUGCCCAGCUGGGCCACGGCCAUGCGUGGGGUGGCCCAAUAAACACCGUGGACUCCCAGCAAGGCUGCUGCCUGGUGUUUCGAGGCUGCUGUGGUCGCAGACAGCCGCCUCGCCUUGGCUCCCUGUCAACAAGGUGGGGGUGGG